AGUCCUGGGCGCGCACAAACCCGGAAGCGGAUCGCGUGGAGUGAAGGUCCUACCACGGCGCGUGAGUUUUGCUCUGCCUUGGAUUAAGUCUGCACUUCCCAGGUCCCCGGCGCUUCUGCCCCUGGGACGUGGGAUCCCCACGGACCUGGAAAUUCUCGCCUGUCUUCCCUUCACCCAGAGCAAAUUGAGACGUCCCGGAGGAAGACCAAGGCAGCCUAUUGGGCCUUCCAGGCAAUCACAUGGGAAUCAGCCACACGUCCUUCCUCCUCACCUCAGAACAUCUCAGAAUAACUUGGUGAAAUGUCUCCCACUGUGAGCCUCAGUGAGCCCACCUGUAACAUAGAGGCCUCGCCCCUGAGCUCUACAAUCCUGUGUCCAGUUGUCUCCUCAGCUGUCUCCUGGGUCAUCAAACAGGCAUCCCCACCUUCAGGUGUCCACGAGUGGCUUUCUAAACCCCCAAACACAUUUCCUUGCAGUCUGCACAUCUCAGAUGAGGGUGACUACGUACUUCCGGAAACGGCCGAACUUGACAGCAUGUAUUUUAAAUUUGUGAAAUAAAUUACUUUAUUUGUAAGUGUUGUAAUUUAUAAUAUAAAGAGAAACUUAGAUGUAUACGUGAAAAGAGUGAGAAGAUACAUCACUUCCAAUUUUUGUUUGUUUGUUUGUUUUUUUGAGAGGAAUUUUCACUCUUGUGGCUGAGGCUGGAGUGCAAUGCCAUGAUAUCAGCUCACUGCAACCUCUGACUCCUGGGAUCAAGGGAUUCUCCUUCCUCAGACUCCCGAGUAGCUGGGAUCACAGUCGACUUUCAAAAUUCUUUAAGGAUUGAUUCCUAAAGACUCAUGUUAUGUGAAGAAGCAGCUCAGAAGAGGAAAGGAAAGGAGCCAGGCAUGGCUCUUCCUCAGGGACGCUUGACUUUCAGGGAUGUGGCUAUAGAAUUCUCAUUGGCAGAGUGGAAAUGCCUGAACCCUUCGCAGAGGGCUUUGUACAGGGAAGUGAUGUUGGAGAACUACAGGAACCUGGAAGCUGUGGAUAUCUCUUCCAAACGCAUGAUGAAGGAGGUCUUGUCAACAGGGCAAGGCAAUACAGAAGUGAUCCACACAGGGACAUUGCAAAGAUAUCAAAGUUAUCACAUUGGAGAUUUUUGCUUCCAGGAAAUUGAGAAAGAAAUUCAUGAUAUUGAGUUUCAGUGUCAAGAAGAUGAAAGAAAUGGCCAUGAAGCACCCAUGACAAAAAUAAAAAAGUUGACUGGUAGCACAGACCAACAUGAUCACAGGCAUGCUGGAAACAAGCCUAUUAAAGAUCAGCUUGGAUCAAGCUUUUAUUCACAUCUGCCUGAACUCCACAUAAUUCAGAUCAAAGGUAAAAUUGGUAAUCAAUUUGAGAAGUCUACCAGUGAUGCUCCCUCGGUUUCAACAUCCCAAAGAAUUUCUCCUAGGCCCCAAAUCCAUAUUUCUAAUAACUAUGGGAAUAAUUCCCCGAAUUCUUCACUACUCCCACAAAAACAGGAAGUAUACAUGAGAGAAAAAUCUUUCCAAUGUAAUGAGAGUGGCAAAGCCUUUAAUUGUAGCUCACUCUUAAGGAAACACCAGAUACCCCAUUUAGGAGACAAACAAUAUAAAUGUGAUGUAUGUGGCAAGCUCUUUAAUCACAAGCAAUACCUUACAUGCCAUUGUAGAUGUCACACUGGAGAGAAACCUUACAAGUGUAAUGAGUGUGGAAAGUCCUUCAGUCAGGUAUCAUCCCUUACAUGCCAUCGUAGACUUCACACUGCAGUAAAAUCUCACAAGUGUAAUGAGUGUGGCAAGAUCUUUGGUCAAAAUUCAGCCCUUGUAAUUCAUAAGGCAAUUCAUACUGGAGAAAAACCUUACAAGUGUAAUGAAUGUGACAAAGCUUUUAAUCAGCAAUCAAACCUUGCACGUCAUCGUAGAAUUCAUACUGGAGAGAAACCUUACAAAUGUGAAGAAUGUGACAAAGUUUUCAGUCGGAAAUCAACCCUUGAGUCACAUAAGAGAAUUCAUACUGGAGAGAAACCAUACAAAUGUAAGGUUUGUGACACAGCUUUCACAUGGAAUUCUCAGCUGGCAAGACAUAAAAGAAUUCACACUGGAGAGAAAACUUACAAGUGUAAUGAGUGUGGCAAGACCUUCAGUCACAAGUCAUCCCUUGUAUGCCAUCAUAGACUUCAUGGUGGAGAGAAAUCUUACAAAUGUAAGGUCUGUGACAAGGCUUUUGCGUGGAAUUCACACCUGGUAAGACAUACUAGAAUUCAUAGUGGAGGAAAACCUUACAAGUGUAAUGAAUGUGGGAAGACCUUUGGUCAAAAUUCAGAUCUUCUAAUUCAUAAGUCAAUUCAUACUGGAGAGCAACCUUACAAAUAUGAAGAAUGUGAAAAGGUUUUCAGUUGUGGAUCAACCCUUGAGACACAUAAGAUAAUUCACACCGGAGAGAAACCAUACAAAUGUAAGGUUUGUGACAAGGCUUUUGCGUGUCAUUCCUAUCUGGCAAAACAUACUAGAAUUCAUAGUGGAGAGAAACCUUACAAGUGUAAUGAGUGCAGCAAGACCUUCCGUCUGAGGUCAUACCUUGCAAGCCAUCGCAGAGUUCAUAGUGGUGAGAAACCUUACAAGUGUAAUGAGUGCAGCAAGACCUUCAGUCAGAGGUCAUACCUUCAUUGCCAUCGUAGACUUCAUAGUGGUGAGAAACCUUACAAGUGUAAUGAGUGUGGCAAGACCUUCAGUCACAAGCCAUCCCUUGUUCACCAUCGUAGACUUCAUACUGGAGAGAAAUCUUACAAAUGUACGGUUUGUGACAAGGCUUUCGUGCGUAAUUCAUACCUGGCAAGACAUACCAGAAUUCACACUGCAGAGAAACCUUACAAGUGUAAUGAAUGUGGGAAGGCUUUUAAUCAACAAUCACAACUUUCACUUCAUCAUAGAAUUCAUGCUGGGGAGAAACUUUACAAAUGUGAAACAUGUGACAAAGUUUUCAGUCGCAAAUCACACCUUAAAAGACAUAGGAGAAUUCAUCCUGGAAAGAAACCAUACAAAUGUAAGGUUUGUGACAAGACUUUUGGGAGUGAUUCACACCUGAAACAACAUACUGGACUUCACACUGGAGAGAAACCUUACAAGUGUAAUGAGUGUGGCAAAGCCUUUAGCAAGCAGUCAACACUUAUUCACCAUCAGGCAGUUCAUGGUGUAGGGAAACUUGACUAAUGUAAUGAUUGUCACAAAGUCUUCAGUAACGCUACAACCAUUGCAAAUCAUUGGAGAAUCUAUAAUGAAUAAAGAUCUAACAAGUGUAAUAAAUGUGGCAAAUUUUUCAGACAUCAUUCAUACAUUGCAGUUCAUUGACACACUCAUACUGGAGAGAAACCUUACAAAUGUCAUGACUGUGGCAAGGUCUUCAGUCAAGCUUCAUCCUAUGCAAAACAUAGGAGAAUUCAUACAGGAGAGAAACCUCACAUGUGUGAUGAUUGUGGCAAAGCCUUUACUUCAUGUUCACACCUCAUUAGACAUCAGAGAAUCCCUACUGGACAGAAAUCUUACAAAUGUCAGAAGUGUGGCAAGGUCUUGAGUCCGAGGUCACUCCUUGCAGAACAUCAGAAAAUUCAUUUUUGAGAUAACUGUUCCCAAUGCAGUGAGUAUAGCAAACCAUCAAGCAUUAAUUGACACUAGAGUCAGUCCAGCAUUGACUUGAGUUUGUGUUGACUUAACAUUGAGUUCAACCCUUAAUUGACAUUCAAGUGUUUAUGUUAAGAGGAUUGGGCCAGGUGUGGUUUCUCACACCUGUAAUUCCAGCACGGUUGGAGGCCAAGGCACAUAGGUCACUUGAGGUCAGAAGUUUGAAACCAGCAUGGCCAACAGAUGUCAGCCACUUUUCCCAGCCUGUUUUUUGAUUCUUAUUUUCUAUUUUUCUUUUUUGAGAUAGUACUUUUUAAAGAGAUAGUACUUUUUUGAUAUAGUACUUUAUAAAAGGGAGAUCAGGCCAGGCACGGAGGCUCAUGUAAGUAAUCCCAGCACUUUGGGAGGCCGAGACGGGCCCAUGACAAGGUCAGGAGAUCGAGACCGUCCUGGCUAACACGGUGAAACCCCAUCUCUACUAAAAAUAUAAAAUAUUAGCCAGGCGUGGUGGCAGGUGCCUGUAGUCCUAGCUGCUUGGGAGGCUGAGGCAGGAGAAUGGUGUGAAUCCUGGAGACGGAGCUUGCAGGGAGCCAACAUCGUGCCACUGCACUCCGGCCUGGGCGACAGUGAGAAUCUGUCUCAAAAAAAAAAAAAAAAAAAGGAUAUCAAAGCUGGAUGGUGGCUCAUCCCUGCAAUCACAACACUUUGGUAGACUGAUGUGAGUGGAUCACCUAAGGUCAGAAGUUCAAGAGCACCCUGGCUAACAUGGUGAAACCCCAUCUCUACUAAAAAUACAAAAGUUAGCCGGGGGGUGGUGGUGUGCACCUUUAGUUCCAGCUACUUGAGAGGCUGAGGCACAAGAGUCGCUUAAACCUGGGAGGUAGAGGUUGCCGUGAGGCAAAAUCGUGCCACUGCCCUCAGCCUGGGCAGUAGAGUCAGUCUCCAUCUCAAAGAAACCAGCAAACAAAAAAUAUUAAAAAAAAACAUUAAAAAUG